AUUACAGGCGUGAGCUACCUCGUCCGGCCCAUCAACAGUAUCUUGAUAGGAGAUACUGUUAGUUGGCGGGUAGUUAUUUCCUACCUUUACUGCUUGGGGGAGAAGGGUUGGGCAGAUGUGCUUUCUACCCAAGGUGGGCGGAGAGUCUGAGGACUGCUGCAGGACUGUUCAUCCCAGUGAUAUGUAAAUUUACUGUAAUUUGCAAGAAGAGUUGCAAAGUUAUUAUUAGGGAAGGAUGGCAGUGACACCUCAUCUGCUACCGUCUGCUCGGAGGGUCCGUGUAAAUUGGGGUUUGCUCUGUAAAACAAAGCUUGGAAGGUCAUGUCAGUAACAGCACCUUAUCUGGCAUCUCCUGGAAUGAGGGGUCCCAGGUAGGAAUUGUCUUUAUAUAACAAGUUUAGACCUUCUGAGGGACUUCUUUAUAAAAUGUAUUACACAAUCCUUUGUCCUUUGUAGGAGGCUAAAUAUUGAUUUCCCAAAGAUGUCCCUAUCCUAAUCCCUGGAACCUGUGAAUGUCAUCUUAUAUAGCAAAAGAGAUUUUGAAGAUGUGAUUAGAGACCUUAAGAUGGGAGAUCAUCCUAGAUUAUCUGGGUGUAACCACACCCAUCCUUAUAAGGCAAAGGCAGGAGGAGUCACCGUCAGAGAAGGCCACGUGAGGACAGAAGCAGAGUUAGAAGCUUUGAAGAUGGAGGAAGGGGCCAGCAACCAAGGAAUGCAGCCCUCCUCUAGAAGCUGGAAAAGGUGUCAAGCUAGGGAUGCGGUCCAUUCCCAUUGCCACUGCUUGCACCAUUUACCAUAAGUUCUUUUGCGAGACCAACCUGGACGCCUAUGACCCUUACCUGAUUGCCAUGUCUUCAAUUUACUUGGCCGGCAAAGUGGAAGAGCAGCACCUGCGGACUCGUGACAUCAUCAAUGUGUCCAACAGGUACUUUAACCCAAGCGGUGAGCCCCUGGAAUUGGACUCCCGCUUCUGGGAACUCCGGGACAGCAUCGUGCAGUGUGAGCUUCUCAUGCUGAGAGUUCUGCGCUUCCAGGUCUCCUUCCAGCAUCCACACAAGUACCUGCUCCACUACCUGGUUUCCCUCCAGAACUGGCUGAACCGCCACAGCUGGCAGCGGACCCCUGUUGCCGUCACCGCCUGGGCCCUGCUGCGGGACAGCUACCAUGGGGCGCUGUGCCUCCGCUUCCAGGCCCAGCACAUCGCCGUGGCGGUGCUCUACCUGGCCCUGCAGGUCUACGGAGUUGAGGUGCCCGCCGAGGUCGAGGCUGAGAAGCCGUGGUGGCAGGUGUUUAAUGACGACCUUACCAAGCCAAUCAUUGAUAAUAUUGUGUCUGAUCUCAUUCAGAUUUAUACCAUGGACACAGAGAUCCCCUAAGGUCCUGGCCCAGGCCUGCCCAAAGAGAAGCCCAGGAUGGUCGGCUGCCUGGGGACAUUGUCACCACGUCGCCAUGACGGCUGGUCCCCACAGGACCAGCUGGGAGGACUGGUUGUGCUGCUGGAGAAGGGCUGGAGAAGGCAAUGGCAUGCUGCCGCUUUGCCAGUCCCUAGAAGUCGCGGUGCAGGUGAUGGUGGGAGCCGCGCCUCCAGCGGGCAGGCCGGGAGUGUACUGUGUGCAGCUGACCCAAGGCAGCCACAUCUGCGUUUGUCCUUUGAGAGGACUUUGACUACAAUACAGGCAUGACAUCAAUGAAAGGAAAGUCAUGAAAUCGAUGAGACUGAAUCCCUACGGAUUUCUUAAAAGCCAGAUUUGUAGGGAGAAUGAAUGUGCAACGUGGCUGAAAUCUAUUUUGUGUAAUAAAAGGUGAUACAAGUCAA